GCCCCUCCGAGGCGCCGUAGCGCGGGAGGGAGGCGGCGGCGCUGUGGUCCGUGGGUCCGCCGGUCCGUGGGUCUGCCCGGCCGCCCGGCCCCGCCCUGCCCCCCGGGGCGGCUCGGCUCCAUGGCCCGCGGCGGCGGCGGCGGCGGCGGCGGCGGGAGGCGACCCGGGGGCCGCGGUGGCCGCUGACCGGGCGGCGGGAGGCGGCGGGGCCGGGCCAUGGGGGACGGAACCGUCCGCAGCCGCCGGAGCCGGGAGCCCUGCCCAAGUCGGAGCGGCGUCCCCUGCUGAGCCCCGAGCGCCGGGCCAGCAGCCGGAUGCCCGGGCCCACUGGGCGGGCCAGUGGCCGCCUGCGGGAUGAGCAGACUGCUGGGGGGGACGCUGGAGCGCGUCUGCAAGGCUGUGCUCCUUCUCUGCCUGCUGCACUUCCUCGUGGCCGUCAUCCUCUACUUUGACGUCUACGCCCAGCACCUGGCCUUCUUCAGCCGCUUCAGUGCCCGAGGCCCUGCCCAUGCCCUCCACCCAGCUGCUAGCAGCAGCAGCAGCAGCAGCAACUGCUCCCGGCCCAACGCCACCGCCUCUAGCUCCGGGCUCCCUGAGGUCCCCAGUGCCCUGCCCGGUCCCACGGCUCCCACGCUGCCACCCUGUCCUGACUCGCCACCUGGUCUUGUGGGCAGACUGCUGAUCGAGUUCACCUCACCCAUGCCCCUGGAGCGGGUGCAGAGGGAGAACCCAGGCGUGCUCAUGGGCGGCCGAUACACACCGCCCGACUGCACCCCAGCCCAGACGGUGGCGGUCAUCAUCCCCUUUAGACACCGGGAACACCACCUGCGCUACUGGCUCCACUAUCUACACCCCAUCUUGAGGCGGCAGCGGCUGCGCUACGGCGUCUAUGUCAUCAACCAGCAUGGUGAGGACACCUUCAACCGGGCCAAGCUGCUUAACGUGGGCUUCCUAGAGGCGCUGAAGGAGGAUGCCGCCUAUGACUGCUUCAUCUUCAGCGAUGUGGACCUGGUCCCCAUGGAUGACCGCAACCUAUACCGCUGCGGCGACCAACCCCGCCACUUUGCCAUUGCCAUGGACAAGUUUGGCUUCCGGCUUCCCUAUGCUGGCUACUUUGGAGGUGUGUCAGGCCUGAGUAAGGCUCAGUUUCUGAGAAUCAAUGGCUUCCCCAAUGAGUACUGGGGCUGGGGUGGCGAGGAUGAUGACAUCUUCAACCGGAUCUCCCUGACUGGGAUGAAGAUCUCACGCCCAGACAUCCGAAUCGGCCGCUACCGCAUGAUCAAGCACGACCGCGACAAGCAUAACGAACCUAACCCUCAGAGGUUUACCAAGAUUCAAAACACGAAGCUGACCAUGAAGCGGGACGGCAUUGGGUCAGUGCGGUACCAGGUCUUGGAGGUGUCUCGGCAACCACUCUUCACCAAUAUCACAGUGGACAUUGGGCGGCCUCCGUCGUGGCCCCCUCGGGGCUGACACUAAUGGACAGAGGCUCUCGGUGCCGAAGAUUGCCUGCCAGAGGACUGACCACAGCCUGGCUGGCAGCUGCUCUGUGGAGGACCUCCAGGACUGAGACUGGGCUCUGUUUUCCAAGGGUCUUCACUAGGCCCCCUAGCUACACCUGGAAGUUUCAGAACCCACUUUGGGGGGCCUCCUGCCUGGGCAGGCUCUUCAAGUGUGGCCCUCUUUGGAGUCAACCCUCCUUCCCGACCCCCUCCCCCUAGCCCAGCCCCAGUCACUGUCAGGGUCGGGCCAGCCCCUGCACUGCCUCGCAGAGUGGCCUGGGCUAGGUCACUCCACCUCUCUGUGCCUCAGUUUCCCCCCCUUGAGUCCCCUAGGGCCUGGAAGGGUGGGAGGUAUGUCUAGGGGGCAGUGUCUCUUCCAGGGGGAAUUCUCAGCUCUUGGGAACCCCCUUGCUCCCAGGGGAGGGGAAACCUUUUUCAUUCAACAUUGUAGGGGGCAAGCUUUGGUGCGCCCCCUGCUGAGGAGCAGCCCCAGGAGGGGACCAGAGGGGAUGCUGUGUCGCUGCCUGGGAUCUUGGGGUUGGCCUUUGCAUGGGAGGCAGGUGGGGCUUGGAUCAGUAAGUCUGGUUCCCGCCUCCCUGUCUGAGAGAGGAGGCAGGAGCCCCAGGGCCGGCUUGUGUUUGUACAUUGCACAGAAACUUGUGUGGGUGCUUUAGUAAAAAACGUGAAUGGA